GCGUCAGCAGCUGCUGUGGAGCCAGGCAGCGUCGGCCGCGUCGGCCGCGGGUUGGAGCAGCUCAGGUGCGGCCCCGCCCCGCCCGCCUGCGGCCCCGCCCCGGCCCAGGUGAGCUGCCCCGCCCCGGCCCAGGUGAGUGGCCCCGCGUCCGCCGGUGUGACCUGAGUCCGCCUGACCACCUGUCCCUCCGGUGGCCCUGGGUGUGCGUGUCCCCAAUCGCGGGGAAGCCUGUAGGGGCGCCACGUCGCCGCCUGGGCAGCGUGUGCGGGUCCGUGGCAACUCUUGGGCCCCCAGCCAGGAAACCUUGACUGCACUAAGAGUUUGCAGGGUGCCCAGGCCCUAGGGACUCUCUGGAGGAUGGGAUGACAGAUGCAGGAGGACCCGGAGAAGGCCCCGACAGAGAUUGUGAGAACAGUAAGUGUGGCCCAAAGAAGAACAUUUUUAAAGAAAUACAACCAUUGGGGAUGAUAGCAGAUUCACAAUGGAGGUUCCCCCAGCAACAAAGUUUGGUGAGACCUUUGCAUUUGAGAACAGGUUAGAGUCACAACAAGGGCUUUUCCCAGGGGAGGACCUGGGGGACCCUUUUCUUCAGGAAAGAGGUUUGGAGCAAAUGGCUGUGAUCUACAAGGAGAUCCCUCUUGGUGAGCAGGACGAAGAAAAUGAUGAUUACGAGGGGAAUUUCAGUUUGUGCUCAAGCCCUGUUCAGCAUCAAAGUAUCCCCCCAGGAACCAGACCCCAGGAUGAUGAGCUCUUCGGACAAACCUUCCUCCAGAAAUCCGACCUCAGCAUGUGUCAGAUAAUCCACAGUGAAGAGCCCAGUCCAUGCGAUUGUGCAGAAACAGACAGAGGGGACUCAGGACCUAACGCACCUCACAGAACCCCACAACCAGCCAAGCCCUAUGCGUGUCGAGAGUGUGGGAAGGCCUUCAGCCAGAGCUCGCACCUGCUCCGACACCUGGUGAUCCACACUGGGGAGAAGCCCUAUGAGUGCUGUGAGUGCGGGAAGGCCUUCAGCCAGAGCUCCCACCUGCUCAGGCACCAGAUCAUCCACACCGGGGAGAAGCCCUACGAGUGCCGGGAGUGUGGGAAGGCCUUCCGCCAGAGCUCAGCCCUCACGCAACACCAAAAGAUCCACACCGGAAAGAGGCCCUACGAGUGCAGGGAAUGCGGGAAAGAUUUCAGCCGGAGCUCCAGCCUCAGAAAACACGAGAGAAUUCAUACAGGAGAGAGACCUUAUCAGUGUAAGGAAUGUGGGAAAUCCUUCAACCAGAGCUCAGGCCUGAGCCAGCAUCGGAAGAUCCACACCCUAAAGAAACCUCACGAGUGCGAUCUCUGUGGGAAAGCCUUUUGUCACAGGUCACACCUCAUCCGACACCAGCGGAUCCACACUGGGAAGAAACCAUACAAAUGCGAUGAGUGCGGGAAGGCCUUCAGCCAGAGCUCCAACCUCAUUGAGCACCGCAAGACCCACACUGGCGAGAAGCCCUACAAAUGCCAGAAGUGUGGGAAAGCCUUCAGCCAGAGCUCCUCCCUCAUUGAGCACCAGCGCAUCCACACCGGUGAGAAGCCCUACGAGUGCUGUCAGUGUGGCAAGGCCUUUUGCCACAGCUCUGCGCUGAUCCAGCACCAGAGAAUCCACACCGGCAAGAAGCCCUACACCUGCGAGUGUGGCAAAGCCUUCCGGCACCGGUCAGCCCUCAUUGAGCACUAUAAAACCCACACCAGAGAGAAGCCCUACGUGUGCAAUCUGUGCGGCAAGUCCUUCCGGGGGAGCUCGCACCUGAUUCGCCAUCAGAAGAUUCAUUCUGGGGAGAAGCUAUAGAAAGAGGAGCCCACACAAAGCUUGAAAGCCUGUGCCAGAUGGAGCCUUUAUUCCACGUCGCGUGGUCUCCAAGACCCCACCUACCUCCCUGAUGCUGAAUGGAAACCUUCCCACCUAAGCGCUCUUGAACAUCCCACUAGCAGGAAGGCCCUGUGUGGCCCUGGGCCAAGCACGCCAGCUCUCAGCAGGUUUUCUGCAUGGAAGGGAAGGUGGGGUGAUAGGGAGGGCAGCCAGAAAAGACAGCUGGCCUUCAGUUUCUCCUUCUUGCAUUUGACUCCCAAGCCUACAGGAUUUCAUUUUGCCCUGUCUUCACAUUUCCCAGAAUCUAGAAGAAUAAAUGCCAAGAGGGAGAAAGUUGAAUUAAACCCAGGAAAAUAUCAGAAGAACUCUUUAAAACAGGCUGCAGUCUGGCACUUUUAGAAGACAGAAACCACACUCACAGUCCAAAGCAGUAGAAGAAAAAUGAAUUCAAAAGUAGAUGUGUCAGCAGCAAAGUAGAAUUUUCUCACUGCGUUGGGCAUUGGUGGGGACAACCAAAACAGGUCUGCAGAGCAAAGGCAGGUCUGGAGGGUGGGUCUUGAGAUUGGGGAUGAGGGUGGUGAGCCCCUGGGCGUGGCCUCUUAACCCUCUCCUUAGCCCUAGGGCAGUUUCCCUCAGACAGCUCUGUUACAGGAGGAUAGAGAUUUGAUCCUGUUGGCCAGAGGAUGUUUGACACCCAGCCGUGACUCAGCCUGGACACCGGACAUGACUGCCCUCCAGGAAUAACCCCUCCCUGAGACAUAGUGUCCCCAAGACCACAGUGUGCCUUGGACAUCAGCAGGGCCUGGGUCUGGUCUGUUCUGGCAAUGAUGCAGCCCUCCUGCCCCAGUGUCAGGGGACCUGGGAAGCUGGGUGGCUUGUUGGAGGAGGCUGUGUUCUAAUCAGAAGGUCUGGGUUCAAGUCCUAGUUCCACCCCCUCCUACCUGGGUGAGCUUGAACAAGUCCUGUAACUUCCCCAGGCUCCAUUCCCCCAUCCAAGAGUUGGGGUAAUGGGAACUGGCCACGUGCCUCUAAGGGUUGGUGCCAGGCUGUCAUUCAGAACACAGCCACUGUGAAAGUGCUUUGGCAACUGUGAGCAGUCAUGGUGACUGAGGACAGAGACCCAGAGUGACCCCUGCCCCACCCCUGUGCAUUUCCACGGACUGGAGAGAUGUUCCCGUCUGGUUUCUGAGCAGUGGGACCUCUCAUUGAACAGGGCUUUCUCUCCCUCCACCCCUUGCAGCCUGGGCUGUGUAUGCCUGCGGAUGCAGUGUCCCACACAAGGACACUUCCUCUAGGAUGCCAUCCUGAGCCUCCUGUAGCAGCAGUGUCAUUCUGCACUUCCACAUUCUGUCUGUCUUCCCCGCCUGCCAACUAGGAGUUCACGUGGGGCUUGUUUAAACAGUACCAUUGCUUGUGUCCCACCUGGACCAGUUCAGUCAGCCCCAGUGGUGGCAUGUUUUAAAGCUCCCCAGGUGAUUAUAACUUCCUAGUGUGCAGCCAGGCUGUGGGCCCUGUGCUGGGCUUUUUUUUUUGAGAUGGAGUGUUGCCCUGUUGCCAGGCUGGAAUGCAGUGGCGUGAUCUUGGCUUACUGCAAGCUCUGCCUCCUGGGUUCAAGCGAUUCCCCUGCUUCAGCCUCCUGAGUAGCUGGGACUACAGGUGCGUGCCACCAUGCCUGGCUAAUUUUUUGUAUUUUUAGUACAGACGGGGUUUCACCAUGUUGGCCAGGAUGGUCUCGAUCUCUUGACCUCGUGAUCUGCCCGCCUUGACCUCCCAAAGUGCCGGGAUUACAGGCAUGAGCCUCCACACCUGGCCCAUGCUGGGUUUUUGUGCAUCCCUCGACAGCUUCCAAUGUCAGCCUGCUGGCUUUGGCUGAGCAGAGCUUGAAGGCCAUUCUGUCUCAGUGCCCUCACUCCCUGCUCCCCGCACCCGGAGCCUCAGGGAUGGGCUCAGGCUGAUGGUCAGCUGGGCGCUUGGAAAGUGUUUGGCUGGGGCCUUGGGGAUCUCUUUAGUCCUGGCUUCCCUUGGGCUCCUCAGAGCUAGUGGGGAAGGAGGCAGUCUAGGCUGUUUUGAAGUUUCCUAAACAUUUAUGGCUGGGCUAACAUGAACUCAUCAUGGUAACACUGGGUAUUUCAGCUGAUCAGAAGCUCAGCAUGGCCAUUAUGCCUAGUUUUGAUGAAUAAACAUGGGAAAGCCAUAACUGUUACUAAGUGGGUCUUGAUAGGCCAGAGAUUUCCAAAUGACAGAUAUGAUGGGCUGGAGAGGUCAUGGUGGGAGUUCCAGCCAUGCCUCUGUCCAGCCCCUGUCUUUGCUACGUAUGUGAAACAUUUAACAUUUAACCAGCACUCCAUUGUCCACCAGAACCCUCUGUGUAACCAGUUGGACUGACUGGAUGGUGCCCUGGGCAUUGCCUGCAAGUGGCCUGUCAUUUCAGGCCUGUCUCUAUCAAGAGUGAAGAGAGAAUGCUAGGAUGCAGUGGGGACAGCAGGCGGCAUCAAGCAGGGGUCCCUGAAAGAUCUACCUCCUCUUUACACCUGCCCCUCUUCCCCACCGUUAUCAUCUGGCAAAUGUCUGUUACCUAUCUUUGGUUUCUCCCUCCCCAUCCUUCCUGCACACCCCAGCCAAAUUGAUUUUUAAAGCAUCAUUUUGCACAAGUCACCACUCUCCUUAAAACCAACUUUCAGGAGCUUUCCUGCACGUAAACCCUCGUUUCAGCCAACCUGGUUUACCCACUCUGAGCAAGCCGCAUGGAGAUCAGGCCGCCCCUGCCCACUCCAGCAUCACUCCCAGCUCAUAAUUCUGUGCUGUUCUUGCAUUUUGAAAUGUGCACUUUCUCCUCCUCUCCCUCCCUCUCUCUUUCUAAUUUUUGUGUAACGUGGAGAUGAAGAUCCCCCCUCUCUCCCAAGGGUUAACAGAUAAACAUGGUAAGACCAGGUUCUUUUUUGGAAGUAUGACCAGAGCCUCAUUCCCUCUGUUCAAAUUCUUUCCUUGUUUUAUUAGUUUUUUUUUUUUUUUUUUUUUUUUUGAGACAGAGUCUCACUGUCACCCAGGCUGGAGUGCAGUGGUGCGAUCUUGGCUUGCUGCAACCUCUGCCUCCCGGGUUCAAGUGAUUCUCCUGCCUCAGCCUCCUGAGUAGCUGGGAUUACAGGCAUGUGCCACCACGCCUGGCUAACUUUUGUAUUUUUAGUAGAGAUGGGGUUUCACCAUGUUGGCCAGGCUGGUCUCGAACUCCUGACCUCCUGAUCUGCCUGCCUUGGCCUCCUGAAGUGUUGGGAUUACAGGCGUGAGCCAUGUGCCCAGCCAGCUUAUUAGAUUUUUUUUUUUAAACUCUCUCAUUCUAUUUAGAUUCUCAAACAGUGUAAAGUUAUAAAAGAUCAUCCCUGGCAAUAUUUUAAUCAAUUAUCUUUUAAUUUAGUUGUUCUUUGUUUUUGUUGUCCUACCUUUUUUUUUCUUUUUUCUUUUUUCUUUUUUUGAGAUGGAGUCUUGCUUUGUCACCCAGGCUGUAGUGCAGUGGGGCGAUCUCGGCUUACUGCAAGCUCUACCUCCCAGGUUCAGACCAUUCUCCUGCCUCAGCCUCCCAAGUAGCUGGGACUACAGGCACCCGCCACCACGCCCGGCUAAUUUUUUGUAUUUUUAAUAGAGACGGGGUUUCACCGUGUUAGCCAAGAUGGUAUCUAUCUCCUGAGCUCGUGAUCCGCCCGCCUCGGCCUCCCAAAGUGCUGGGAUUACAGGUGUGAGCCACCGCGCUCGGCAUUUUUUUAUUUCUUCUUCUCCUUAGAGUGACAGCUUUGUCUGCACUCCGUAAGUUUUGACGUGGUGUUUUUUGUUAUAGUAUUAAGAAUUUCCUUUUGCCCAAAUGUUAUUAUUUAAAAAUAUUUCUAAGUGGGCCGGGCAUGGUGACUCACACCUGUAAUCCCAGCACUUUGGAAGGCCGAGGUGGGUGGAUCACGAGGUCAGGAGUUUAAGACCAGCCUGGCCAACAUGGUGAAAACCCGUCUCUACUAAAAAUACAAAAAUUAACUGGGCAUGGUGGCGGGUGCCUGUAAUCCCAGCUACACGGGAGGCUGAGGCAGGAGAAUCGCUUGAACCCGGGAGGCGGAGGUUGCAGUGAGCCAAGAUUGUGCCACUACCCUUCAGCCUGGGUGACAGGGCAAGACUCCAUCUCGGGGAAAACAACAACAACAAAAACAAAAAAUAGCCGGGAGCGGUGGCUCAAGCCUGUAAUCCCAGCACUUUGGGAGGCCAAGACGGGCAGAUCAUGAGGUCAGGAGAUCGAAACCAUCCUGGCUAACACGAUGAAACCCUGUCUCUAUUAAAAAUACAAAAAAUUAGCCGUGCGUGGUGGCUACAGGCAGCUGUGCGCCUGUAGUCCCAGCUACUUGGGAGGCUGAGGCAGGAGAAUGGUGUGAACCCGGGAGGCAGAGCUUGCAGUGAGCCGAGGUGGUGCCACUGCACUCCAGCCUGGGCAAAAGAGCUAGACUCUGUCUCAAAAAAAAUAUAUAUAAAAAAAAUUUCUAAGUGAUGAAUGCUUAGGGUAUUGCUGCUUAUUUCUUACUGUACUGUGGUGUCAACAUUUCUAAGUGUCCAUAGGACUUCUUUGGGCCUGAAUAUAUUAUCAGUUUUUAUAAAAGCAUUUGUGUAAUCUCAAAAUGUGUUUUUAUUCUACCAGUUCUAUUUGUUAACUCAAUUUUUUCAUUAUUUUAUUCAAAUCCAUAUUUUCUCUGACUUUCAUUUACUUUAGAGUUCUUAAUCUGGGGGUCCAUGGCCUGCCUAGGAGUCUUUAGCAUGUAGGGGUUUAGGAGUUGCAGACCCCUAGGGAUCGAACAAAGCUGGGUAUGUGCUUGAAGGAAUUUUGCUGGGACAAGGAUCUGUAGUAUUUACUAUAUUUUUAAAUGCCUCUGUGACACCAAAGCAGUUCAGAACACUCAUUUACCUGAUCUAAUCAUAGUUUGAUGUUUGUGUGUUAUAUCUCUAUGUAUUCCUGUUUCACUUUUAAUUUCUGUAUGUGUAUUGUCGCUAUGUUGUGCAGUUUUUCUCAAGUCAUUUUUGAGAAAUAGGCAGGGUAUGAAUUAUCAAUAAAUAAGUAUCAUGUUUGGGGCA